ACUAAGUUUCUGUCUGGUAUCAUAUUCUGAAUGCUGAAGAACUUCAUUUAACAUUUCUUAUAACACUUGUCUUCUGGCAAUGAAUUUUCUCAGCCUUUAUCUGCCCUUCUGCCCUGCUCUUGUUCUUCUCCCCACAGUGGACUUCGCUGUGUUAUUUUUUGGUGCUGGGUGGGCUGAUGGUGAGGGGUAUGGGAGAAGGAUCUCUGUUGUCUUGUUCCAUUCGCCCUCUUAUGUAGGGUUUCUCUGCCUGGGCACUGGGAGUUGGGCUUUCUCAAUAUGCCUGCUCCUCUUCCCUAGGAGAGCUAAUCUUUUAACUUGUGUCAGUGGUUGGUCUUUUGUGGGUGAACAUUUCUUGUCCCUUCCCCAGUGGUAGGAGUCCUUUGAUGGUUGUGGUCUAAGUGCUUGAGCCUGUACUGUUUCUUUCCCUUCUCCCCGCAGUGGUGGAUCUUUACUGGGGUCAUCCUGGGGAUGACAUAGUUUAUUGCUUUUCUUCAGUAGCUAAAGGCUUUCUUCUGAUAUGAGAAAAAGGUCAGGACAGGAGGUGUACACUGUCAUGCCAUUCUUGCAGCAGCUGCUGUUCCGCUCUUGCAUGACAGCAUCACUGAGGAAGUCUCUUUGUUCUCCCAUCUGUUCCCAAACCUCUCUCACAUGGGGAGGUCCUUGGAAAAUAAUGUGAACAUGCCUGUGAGCAUCUCUUGGGUCUGGGGCUUGCUGUAGUUCUAUACCUUCAUUCUGUCUCACAUUCCUCCUUUAGCAAGUUGUUAAAAUGUUAGUUGAUUUUUUACUUGUUUGGAUGGUGGAUGGAGUAGGGCACUGGCCACAGGUAAGCUAGUGCUCUCCUUAAGAAAAGUUAUGAUUUUGCAGUUUAUCAUUCUCAUUGUUAGGAUAGUAGUGAUACUCUUACUAACCUUCUUGGUGGAAACUGAACUUUUAUAUAUUUUUUAUUUCAAUAGCUUUAGGGGUACAAGUGGUUUUUGGUUACAUGGAUGAAUUGUAUAGUGGUGAAGUUUGAGAUUUUGGUGUACCACUCACUGAGUAAUGUAUAUUAAAUCCAAUAUGGAGUUUGGAUAACCCUCCUAGCCUGUCUCUUCCGAGUGUCCAGUGUUCAUUAUACCACUCUGUAUGCCUUUGUGUACCCACAGCUUAGCUCCCAUUUGUAAGUGAGAAUGUGUGGUAUUUGGUUUUUCAUUCCUGAGUUACUUCACUUAGAAUAAUGGCCUCCAGCUAGAUCCAAGCCGCUGCCAGAGACAUUAUUUUGUUAUUUUUUAUGGCUGAAUAGUAUUACAUUGUGUAUAUAUACAUUUUCUUUUAUCCACUCAUAGGCUGAUGGGCACUUAGGUUGAUUCCAUCUCUUUAUGAUUGUGAAUUGGGCUGUGAUAAACAUACAUGUGCAGGUGUCUUUUUGAUACAAUGCAGUUGAUACAAAGCAUUUCCUCUGCUUGCACUCACUCCAUCCUGCAGCCCUUGGAAGAAGGUGCGUGCUUCUCUUUUGCCUUCCACCAUGAUUCUGUUUCCUGAGGCCUCCCUAGCAAUGUGGAACUGUGAGCCAAUUAAACCUCUUUCCUUUAUAAAUUACCCAGACUUAGGGAAGUUCUUUAUAGCAGUGUGAGAAUAGAUUAAUACACUUCUCAUCCCUUUAAAAAAAUACUCUGGAGUUAUGGUUUUAUAUGUGAGGUUUCCUGGAUCUGUUCUCUAAAUAUCAUAUUUUUAUCUGGUCAUGGUUUUCACUUGAGAUUUUGUUUUUGAAUUUGAUUCUAAAUAUCAUAUUUUUAUCUGUUCGUAGUUUUCACUUGAGAUUUUUUUUUGAAUUUGAUUCUUAUCUCUUUCUUUCAAUUCAUUCUGUAAAGAUAUUUAAUUGGGAAGUUAAUGGUUUUUAACUCUUAAAAGUUUUUUUUUUUUUGAGUGCUGUAUUUGAAUCUCCUUAAAUUUUCUUAGAUAAUUCAGGUAUUCCCUUUAGUUGAGGUAUUCUGUCUGCUGCAGAACACAGAGCGUGGGUCUAAUUCUUCUGCCUUAUCUUCCUUUUUCUAGCAGCUCUGCUCCUUUGUAUGGGCUGUAUCCCUUGGUUGACUCAUUGGAGCUCAAGACUGUUAUUGAAUAGUCCUCUGUGGCGUCAGUCCUGCAGGUGGUAGAAGGCAAAUGGGUCUCUCUUCAGUGGGCCUGCACUGGCAGAUAGGCUGUCAGUUCCCUGUCAGUCAGCUUUCUGGUCUCCUUGUACUUUUGUGGGCAUCAAGAGCAGGAAAGAUUGUGGGCUGUGACCCCCUCCAUCUCUGACUUUCAAAUUCUUUUUGGGAUUCCCUGGUUUUCAGUCCUUGUCCCUGGUUACUCUGCUGUCCUCUACUUUAUUACUAAGUCUACUGGAGAGAACACCUCACACCAGAUUUCUGCCAGAACCUAAGGCUUCACUUGCAUCCAUUUGCCCACAGAUGCUAGUAGUAGUUGUUUUGCUCAAGAGAGGAAAGUAACAGGUUUGAGGGUGAAGGGGAAAGGUGUUGCAUUCAGGUCACCAUAUACCCACAAUUCUUUUUGUCGCAUCUCUUCUGCAUUUCCGUUUUGUAUUAUUUCAUAAGUGAUGCAUUUCAUAAAGAAUAAUUCCAUUUUAUUAUAGGCACCACUACAUUUCUUUCCCCUGACCUCUGCUAUAUCAACUGGAGUAAGAGAGACAACUGCAGUAAUUAAACUUGAAGUUUUUGUUCUCCCUCUAACAGGAAGCUGGCAGAUGGAACAAGAUGUUUGUGGCCAUUAGUUCAGUGGCUCAAAAUGUCAGGGCAGAAGUCUUUGCAAUUCUCUUGGACUCAAGGUGGCUGCUUCAGCCCCAGCUAUCAUGCUCAUAUUCCAGGGUGAAAAGUUCGGACCCUUUGCUGGAGAGAAGAGAAUGCCUGAAGACUUGGAUGAAAAUAUGGAUUACAGGUUGAUGUGGGAGGUUCGUGGGAGUAAGGGAGAAGUUUUGUACAUUUUGGAUGCUACCAACCCACGGCACUCCAACUGGCUUCGCUUCGUUCAUGAGGCACCAUCUCAGGAGCAGAAGAACUUGGCUGCCAUUCAAGAAGGAGAAAACAUUUUCUAUUUGGCAGUUGAAGAUAUAGAAACAGACACGGAGCUUCUGAUUGGCUACCUGGAUAGUGACAUGGAGGCUGAGGAGGAAGAACAGCAAAUUAUGACAGUCAUCAAAGAAGGGGAAGUUGAAAAUUCUAGAAGACAAUCAACAGCGGGCAGAAAAGAUCGCCUUGGCUGUAAAGAGGACUAUGCUUGUCCUCAAUGUGAAUCGAGUUUUACCAGUGAGGAUAUUCUUGCUGAGCAUCUCCAGACAUUGCACCAGAAACCCACAGAGGAGAAAGAAUUUAAGUGCAAGAACUGUGGGAAGAAAUUCCCAGUUAAGCAGGCUUUGCAAAGACAUGUUCUUCAGUGCACAGCGAAAAGCAGUCUAAAGGAGUCUUCGCGAAGUUUUCAGUGCUCUGUUUGCAAUUCUUCCUUCAGUUCAGCAUCGAGUUUUGAGCAGCACCAGGAGACUUGCCGGGGGGAUGCCAGGUUUGUGUGCAAGGCUGACAGCUGUGGAAAGAGGCUGAAGAGCAAGGAUGCCCUGAAAAGACACCAGGAAAAUGUCCACACUGGAGAUCCUAAGAAAAAGCUUAUAUGUUCAGUGUGCAAUAAAAAGUGUUCUUCAGCAUCAAGCCUACAGGAACAUAGAAAGAUUCAUGAGAUAUUUGAUUGUCAAGAAUGUAUGAAGAAAUUUAUUUCAGCUAAUCAGCUAAAACGUCAUAUGAUCACCCACUCAGAUAUGAGAUUGUCUCCACUCAUUUUUUUAAUAGAAAAACGACCCUAUAAUUGCGAGAUUUGUAAUAAGUCUUUCAAGAGGCUUGAUCAAGUGGGUGCUCACAAAGUAAUACACAGCGAAGACAAACCUUACAAAUGCAAACUUUGUGGAAAGGGAUUUGCCCACAGAAAUGUUUACAAGAAUCAUAAGAAGACCCACUCUGAGGAGAGACCGUUCCAAUGUGAAGAAUGUAAAGCUUUGUUCCGGACCCCAUUUUCUUUACAGAGACACCUGCUAAUACAUAACAGUGAGAGGACUUUCAAGUGCCAUCACUGCGAUGCUACCUUUAAGAGGAAGGAUACAUUAAAUGUUCAUGUCCAGGUGGUUCAUGAAAGACACAAGAAGUAUAGGUGUGAGCUAUGUAAUAAGGCCUUUGUUACACCUUCAGUGCUUAGAAGUCAUAAGAAAACACAUACAGGAGAAAAGGAGAAAAUCUGUCCAUAUUGUGGCCAGAAAUUUGCCAGCAGUGGUACACUCAGAGUUCAUAUCCGGAGCCACACAGGUGAGCGUCCCUAUCAAUGUCCUUACUGUGAAAAAGGAUUCAGUAAAAAUGAUGGACUGAAGAUGCACAUUCGUACUCACACCAGGGAGAAGCCGUACAAGUGCUCAGAGUGCAGCAAGGCCUUCAGCCAGAAGCGAGGCCUGGAUGAGCACAAGAGGACGCACACUGGAGAAAAGCCUUUUCAGUGUGAUGUUUGUGAUUUGGCUUUUAGCCUGAAGAAAAUGCUGAUUCGACACAAGAUGACUCAUAAUCCCAAUCGUCCCCUGGCAGAAUGCCAGUUUUGCCAUAAGAAGUUUACAAGGAAUGACUACCUCAAAGUGCACAUGGACAAUAUCCAUGGUGUAGCUGACAGCUAAUAGGGGCUGUAAAGGAAUUAAACUAUUCAGAAGGGCUCCUAAUAUGAAUCCCAGAUUUUUAUCACCUGAUCAGCAUAACAGAAGUAGCCAAAAGUGACUUACUGGUCUCAUAGUUCUUAUUUGCCUACAUUUAGAGUCUGUAGAUGCAUAUGCAACCAAAAAAAAGUCUUACUUUUAACAAGAAAUGGUAUAAAUGGAAAAAAAAUACAACUCCAUAGCCUUGCAAAAUGCAACUUGUGCUCUGUCUUAUAAAAAUGGAGAAAGGAGUCAUGGCUCUCUUUCUUGGCCAUCCCUCUGUAAUGAAGUUUAUAAUAUACUUCCCUAAUAGGCCUUUUUAUUUUAUUGUUAUUCUUUGUGUGUCUGUGUGUCUGUGUGUCUGUAUGUGUCUGUGUGUGUGCACUCACUUGCAAAUGCCAGUUGUUGCAGCUGGUUUUACCAAUUUAAAUAGAAAUAAAUCAAGAUAUCCAACUAUUUCUUUGCAGAUGAGGAUAAGAAUAAGUUAUCAAAGUCUCAAGUUUGAUAGGAAAAUAAAUAGUUGCUAUUUUAUAAGACAAACCAAGAGCUGAGCUUAUCUAAUAGCUCUGUGCAACAAAUGAGUUUAAAAUAGAUAUUUGAUAACUAAAACAUCUAUUAAAAUAUUGCUCAUUUUAGAGGAUUCUUAGGAAACAUUAUUUAUUCUCAUCAUUCAGAUGCAGACAUUCAUGGUCUGGAAUACUUUUAUAAGUUCUACACAAAAAUGACCAUCACAUUUAAAUAUUCAGCAGGCUACCCCUCUUGAAUUUAGACCAUUUAGCUUUAGAAAUUAACAGUAUACCAAUAUAUAUAAUUAAAAAUAGAAACCAAAUAGAUUCUCUGUAUUUGGCAACAGAGUGGCAGAACAAUAGUGGCAUCUCCACAUUUGUUAGGAUGAACAUAGCCCUUUCCCCUCUCCUUCCAUAAAAGUGCACAGAACAUGUUAGUGCAGAUACAGUCCUCAGAACAUUAACAUUCCAUUUUGCAAAAGACAUUUUCCAGAAUCUUGGCAGUAGGUAAUUCUGAAACACUUUUGAAUUACCUUCAAUCAUCCCAUAUAAUUAGGAAUCCAGAAUACAAAGUACAAACUUGGCAAUUGUUAUGAUUGAAACUGUCACUGAUGCUUAAGGGAAAUUGAAGCAAGAAGCAUAAUUUCUUCCUUUAGGUUAUAUUUCAGCAAAAUACUUGACAGCAACAUACAAUGAACAGCUUGUUUGGAGAGAUGAUAUGAUACAAUGUAAUAGUGAUGUCAAAAUAACCUGGAGGAAUAUCCAAAAACCAGAAAAACGUUAAAAUGAAGCCCAACUCAUGAACCUCUCUAACUGAAGCCCAGUCAAAAGAAAGGAAGUAUAGUUUUAAGGAAGUUAUUUGGUUCUAAUGAGUUAAGGAGAAAGGUUAUCUGAGACACAGUUCUUUGACUUCAGGAAUCUCAUUUUAGAAUUAUAUUCAUGCCCAGUUCCAGUUUUAAAAAGAAACAUAAAGAUUCAAUGUAGACAUUUGAAUGUUGUAAAAUACUAAAUUUGAAACUCAGAAGAGAUAACUUUUAAAAACAUAAAUCCUAAAAUUAUAGUUUAGAAGAUAUUUAAGUAUAGUUAUAUGUAGUAUUUUGAAUCUGAAAUUAUAGACUGUAUUUUAUAAAAAUAAAUUUUGGUCUUGUUUCUCACUAUAUCAUUUGUUUCAACAAUAUAUUUUUAGAUCUAAAGUGUUUUCAUUUUAAUAUGAUAGUGUGUUUAAUAUCAUUUGAAUAUAAAAAGACAGCUGUAAAAUUUGAUAGUGUGUAUUAUUUAAGCACAUCCUGUAUAUUUCUUUGAAUGCUGCUUUCUCUAUAUGGGAUGCUUUAUAUCCCGAUUAUGUGAUGAAUGUAAAACUUGAAAGGAGUCCAAAUUCCAAUUUUGUGUAAUCUCAGUGAGUCACAGUUCACAUGGCUGCUGGGGAAAUUACCCUGAAAACUGUGGUGUCGCUAUGCUGUGGAGUAAACAGACAGGCAAGAGGUGCUGGGCUUUAUCCUGCUGAAGGUUUAUAGACAUGGAAAUCUUUAGAAAAUGGUGUAGAAGGACCUACACCAGAGAGUGGUACACCACUCUCUCCUUUCAGAGGACUGAAACCAAAACAAGUCCUUAGUAGACUAUUUGUAUGCUGUAAAUUUUUAUCCAAAAGACAAGUAUUCAUGGGUAGUUUCAGAUAUAUUAGCAUUUGCUUGCUAAAACUUUUAAAUUACUUAGUAAUAACCAAAAAAAGACACUAUUUUAGGCAUGAUUGAUCAAUUGAAAGCAUAGAUAAUCAUAAGGAAAAGUCUUACAGACAAGCUGAAGUACAGGUACCUACUUUGAAAUGUCUUCUGUUUCCUGCUGUGAAAGAUUUUGGCUGGGGUAUUUUCUUGAGAAAAGACCAGACCCUUAGGUGCCUAUAAAGUCUAAGUAAUUGAGACUUAGAAAUUGGCUAAGUAAAUUUAAGAGACGUUCAAUAAUGUAGGUGGGUUCAGAUACCCUUUUAUAAUAACUGUCUUCUUAGUAUAUUAACACUCAAGAUGUUUGUGUAUCUUUAAUUUGCCUUUGUUUCACAAUAACUGGCUUUUGUUUUCCUUUUCAUGGUGUGUUGUUGGCUAUAUAGAGGCAUUUAUUGGUAAAUUAUAAUCAGCAGUUGCACCAUGGAAGUAUUCUUGGUGAUAAAUUCUUGGGGUUACAUAGUAUAGUUAACAUGUUAUUUUCAAGAAACAUGAGUGUGUGUGUCUGUGUGUGUGUGUCUGAAGAGUAUCACUUAUAUGCAGUGCAUAUACAUGUAAGUGCAUUACUUUGCUCAAAUAUCUUCUGACCUAUUACAGUCAACUCAUGCAUGAGUGUGAACAUGUAUUACAGAAGGUCUUACAGCCUUAGUUUCUGUUUUAGAUUUUAUGUGCUGCUUCCUUUCUCAAACAAAAGCAUGAAAGGAAAGAGGAUAAGUACUAGAAAUAUUCAUUUUUUUCCUUCACAAAUCUAAAUGUUGCUUAUGAAAACUCAUCUUAGAGUAAUGAAUAUGUGGAAGUGGGUAGGUAGGAGGAAAUGUGCCUCUUUAAAAUCCUAAAAUUUUACCAUUGAUAUUGACAUUUGUUUGCGUGUAUAUAAAUGGAGCAUGUGUAAAUAUAGAAUUCCAAUAGCAUUUUUUAUUUUAUUAUAAAUCUAUAAUAAAUAUAUAUAAAUCACUACCA